AUGGGCGGGCGGGCGGGAGGACCGGGACGGCGGCGGCUCCCGACGCGGCGCCGCUGCCCUCCCUCCCCGAGCCUGCAGCCUACGCGAGCCCCGCGGGGCUUUCUGGAGGGCGGGCCCGGCGGCCAAUCAUCGCUCCCACCUGGCCCGAUUGACAGCAGGUGCCCGGGGCUGGCUGCGCGAAGGGGGCGGGGCCUCCGGAGGCUGGCCAGCCAAUUGAGGUCGUCCGGAAAAAAGUGGUCGCGGCGUUGCCAAGAUGAAAUUGUGCUCCAAGUGUUUUCCAAGGUUCCGUAUGACCCAUCAUUUGAUGAAACAAGAACAGCAGUCAGAUCCAUUACAAAGAGAGACACACAAAAAAGCUAUUCCCAACAGAAGAGCUUGAACAAUGCUGCAUUUGCAUCAGGUUCAAAUGAGCGAGAGGAACAUUUGGCUAAAAUAUUUGACACUUAAGGAAACUUUUAUCAGGUCAUUGACUAACUUCAGAGAUAAGAAAACAGAAAAUUCAGCACUUUCACACAACAAGAAGUACGCACUUUGCAAAACUAGUUUGGAAAAGUUACAAAAAGAUGGCUUCAGCCUUCAAUAAGCAAAAAUCAACAAUCACUGAAAGAGAGGAUUAGAUUUCCAGAGUUAUCAAAAUGUAAUACACAGAAUGUCCAUCUCUCAACGUAAAAUUAUAAAACAUACAAAGAAACAGGAAAGGAUGGCUCAUUCACAGGAAAAAGGAAUUUGGCAGAACUUGUUCCUGAGGAAACCUGGGAAUUAAAAUUAUUACACAAGAUGUUAAAUCAACCAUCUUCAAAAUGUUCACUGAACUAAAGGAGACCAUGAACAAAUAACUUAAGGAAAUCAGGAAAACAAUGUAUAAAUAAAAUAAUAUCAAUAAAGAGAUAGAAAUUAUUGAAAAGAGCCAAAGAAAAGUUCUAGAGCUGAAAAGUGUAAUAAAUGAAUACUUGGCACAUGCCUGUAAUCCCAGAACUUUGGGAGGCCGAGGCAGAUGGGUCAUGAGGUCAGGAGAUGAAGACCAUCCUGGCUAACACGGUGAAAUCCCGUCUCUACUAAAAAUACAAAAAAUUAGCAGGGCGUGGUGGUGGGUGCCUGUAGUCCCACCUACUCGGGAGGCUGAGGCAGGAGAAUGGCAUGAACCCAGGAGGCAGAGCUUGCAGUGAGCCGAGAUCGCGCCAUUGCACUCCAGCCUGGGCAACAGAGCAAGACUCUGCCUCAAAAAAAUAAAAAAAAAAAGAAAGGAUCAGCACACUUGAAGAUAAGACAUUGAAAGUAUCCAGCCUGAGAAGCAGAAAGAAAAAAAAAAAAGAAAAUGAAUUGAACAUGUGGGACUUGUGGGGCACCAUCAAGCAUACUAAAAUAUACAUUAUGGGAGUCUCAGAAGGGAAAGACAGAGAGAUAUGAAGACAAUGUUUGAAUGAAGAAUAGCCCCAAACUUCCUGAAUAUGUUGAAAGACAUGAAUGUGCACAUUCAAGUUACUCAAUGAACUCCAAGCAGAAUACUCAGAGAUUCACAGUGAAACACAUUAUUAGCAAAUUGUCAAAAUCCAGACACAAAGAGAAUCUUGAAAGCAGUAACAGAUAAGUGACUCAGCAUAAAAGGAACCCUCAAUAAAAUUCACCACUCAUUUCUCCGCAACAACCACAGAGGGUAGGAGGCAGUAGGAUGGCACAUUCAAAGUUCUGAAAGAAAAAUAAUGUAAUCAGCAGGGCAUGGUGGCUCAUUCCUGUAAUCCCAGCACUUUGGGAGGCUGACGUGGGCAGAUCACUUGAGCCCAGGAAUUCGAGACCAGCCUGGGCAAUACGGCAAAACCCUGUUUCUACUAAAAAAAAAAAAAAAAAAAAAUUAGUUGGGUGUGAUGGUGCACACCUGUAGUCCCAGCUAUUCAGCACACUGAGGUGGGAGGAUCACCUGAGCCUGGGAAGUCCAGGCUGCAGUGAGCUGAGAUUGCCCCACUGCAUUCCAGCCUGGGUGAUGGGAGUGAGAUCCUUUCUUGGAAAAAAAAAAAAAAAGUAAAAAGGAAAAUACUGUCAAGCAAGAAUUCUCUAUCUGACAAAAUUAUCUUUCCAGAAUAAAAGAGAAACAGAACAUUUUCAGGUAAACAAAAGCUGAGAGACCCGCCUUAUGAGAAAUGGCAAAGAGAGCCCUUCAGGCUGAGAUGAAGGGACAUUUAACAGUCACUUGACAUAAGAAAAAAAAAAAUGCUGGUAAAGGUAACUACUAGCUCUAAAAGUCUUAUUGUACUUUAGGUUUCAUCUAUAACUUCUGCCUUUUAAAAAUAUGAUUUAAAAGGUGAAUGCAUGAAAUAAUAAUUACACAUCUGUUAAUGGUCAUACAGUGUAUAAAGAUAGACUCUGUAAUAACAACAAUAUAAAGGGAAGGGAAUAGA